UAAAUCCUAGCCCCAUGACUAUCAAGCUGAAUGACACUUGCGACUUGAGACAUUCCCUAAGCUUUAAUUUUUUUAUCUGUAAAAUAGCAAUAAUAAUAAUGUUUACCUCAAGUGUUGUUAGGAUUAAAUAAGAUAAUCCAUAUAAAAAGUUUUAAUACGGUGUCACAGUAAGUGUUCAGUAACUGUUAGCUGUUAUUAUCUUUUUUUCAGUGAAAAGUGCAUCAGUCGUCUCAUUUACCUAACUCCCUAUAUGUCCAAUGAUCAUUGCUUUAGCUGCCUAAAAGAAUCAGUGAAGUUAUAGAAUGUAAAUUUAGCUAUUUGACUUUAAAAUCUACUUUUUUAACAGCUUUAUUGAGGUCUAAUUGACUUAUAGUAAGCUUAACCUAGUCAAAGUGAAUAAGUUUAUGCCACAAUUUAUAUGUUCAUUUACCUGUUGAUAUUUAGAUUUGUUUUCUGUUUGGGGCUGUUACAAAUAAAACUAUUGUGAACAUUCAUGUAGCAAGUCCUUAAAUGGACAUAUGGACAUAAUACUUUUUUCUUUUCUUUCUUUUUUUUUUUUUUUUGACAUAAUACUUUCAUUUCUCUUAGGUAAAUGCCUAGUUGUGGAAUGGCUGGGUCAGAUGAGUUUUCCAGAAAAAGACCUUCUGCACUGUCCAUCUAAGGAUGCAAUUGAAGCUCAUUUUAUGUCAUGUAUGAAAGAAGCUGAUGCUUUAAAACAUAAAAGUCAAGUAAUCAAUGAAAUGCAGAAAAAAGAUCACAAGCAACUCUGGAUGGGAUUGCAAAAUGACAGAUUUGACCAGUUUUGGGCCAUCAAUCGGAAACUCAUGGAAUAUCCUGCAGAAGAAAAUGGAUUUCGUUAUAUCCCCUUUAGAAUAUAUCAGACAACGACUGAAAGACCUUUCAUUCAGAAGCUGUUUCGUCCUGUGGCUGCAGAUGGACAGUUGCACACACUAGGAGAUCUCCUCAAAGAAGUUUGUCCUUCUGCUAUUGAUCCUGAAGAUGGGGAAAAAAAGAAUCAAGUGAUGAUUCAUGGAAUUGAGCCAAUGUUGGAAACACCUCUGCAGUGGCUGAGUGAACAUCUGAGCUACCCGGAUAAUUUUCUUCAUAUUAGUAUCAUCCCACAGCCAACAGAUUGAAGGAUCAACUAUUUGCCUGAACAGAAUCAUCCUUAAAUGGGAUUUAUCAGAGCAUGUCACCCUUUUGCUUCAAUCAGGUUUGGUGGAGGCAACCUGACCAGAAACACUUCGCUGCUGCAAGCCAGACAGGAAAAAGAUUCCAUGUCAGAUAAGGCAACUGGGCUGGUCUUACUUUGCAUCACCUCUGCUUUCCUCCACUGCCAUCAUUAAACCUCAGCUGUGACAUGAAAGACUUACCGGACCACUGAAGGUCUUCUGUAAAAUAUAAUGAAGCUGAAACCUUUGGCCUAAGAAGAAAAUGGAAGUAUGUGCCACUCGAUUUGUAUUUCUGAUUAACAAAUAAACAGGGGUAUUUCCUAAGGUGACCAUGGUUGAACUUUAGCUCAUGAAAGUGGAAACAUUGGUUUAAUUUUCAAGAGAAUUAAGAAAGUAAAAGAGAAAUUCUGUUAUCAAUAACUUGCAAGUAAUUUUUUGUAAAAGAUUGAAUUACAGUAAACCCAUCUUUCCUUAACGAAAAUUUCCUAUGUUUACAGUCUGUCUAUUGGUAUGCAAUCUUGUAACUUUGAUAAUGAACAGUGAGAGAUUUUUAAAUAAAGCCUCUAAAUAUGUUUUGUCAUUUAAUAACAUACAGUUUUGUCACUUUUCAAGUACUUUCUGACUCACAUACAGUAGAUCACUUUUUACUCUGUGUUACCAUUUUGACUGGUCGUCAUUGGCAUGGGGUGGAUAUAGGGCAUAGGAUUACUUGUCUCAGAAGCUGUCAUAGAAUUUCUUGCUGCCAAUUAAAAAACCUGUGUUCUUUACACACUACACGUAUAAAUAUUGUAACUGUUCAUCUUUGUUGUUUUAUCACUGUAAGCCUGUCAAAUCAUAGUAUCCUAAGCAUCUGUAAAUGCUAAUUUUGCAUUUUUGGAAAAACCCAUUCCUUCCAAGCUAGUGUUUUUCAUUGGCUCCAGGUCUAAUUUUUCACUGUGGUCCCUGGCAGCCAGUCUUUUGAAGUUUAAAGAUUACCUGUCUCUUGACUGCAGUACCUUUUCUUUAAUUUUUACCAAAAAUAUCCAGAGGUUACUGGAGUUCUUAUUCAAUAUAAGGAAAGUUUGCUGCACUUUAUUACCAAGCCUCUGGGAUUUUACCAGUCAAACAUAUUUGUGCAUUACAUUUCAUUUCUUGUGAGCUAGCUGGCUGUCCAUAUUGAAUGUUGACCCAUUUGAGUACGCUAAAAGGCUUACAGUAUCAGACACGAUCAUGGUUUUAGAUCCCAUAAUAAAAAUGAAUGUUUUUCUUAUAAAAAAUUAUACAAAUGCUGAAGUGAGAUUCUACUAUUGUUCAUUGCUUCCUUUUCUUUUUCCUUUUGCGAUUUUCACUGAUUAAUAGCACAUUUCUUCACAAAAUUAGAUAAAGUUGGUCAAAGACCAGAUAUUCUGGAAUGGAAAUUGUAAAGCUUAAUCAAAAAGAAUAGCCAGUACAGCAUACAAUCUCAGAAACUUAGAAGCAAGUAGAAAAUAAUUGGUUGAUGUAAACGAAAGUGCCAUUUUAGUAAAGGCAGGAAAAAAAUAGCAAUAUUUGAGUUAUGUAAGGAUAAAAAAUCCACUGACUUGUAUUUUUGCACAAGAGGCUGGUCUGAAUAUGAUUGUUCACAUUAAGAGUGUUUAUUCGUCGGUUCAUUUUGGGGAUUUUCCCCCUUGAUGUUUUGACAGAUUGAAGUGAGCUUUAGUGAGCAAAAGGAUCAGAAUGCAGGGAACACUAAGCUGUGAUGAAGAAAGUGUGGUAAAAAGCCAGAGUAGUUUUAUACAGACAAAACCAGUGUCAGGCCUUUGCAGUAGGCUUGAGUGAACUUCUGAUCUAGAUUUGAAAGUAAAUUUUAUGAAGACAUUGCCCAUUUUUACUUCCUCAUUCAUUAUUGUACCAGCAUCAUAGCUUUAUUACUCUAAUCCCAGGUAAGUCAAGCCUACAAUGCCCUAGAGGAAGAGUAAAACCAGAAAUUCAUGCUGGCUUAAAUAAUCUAUUUUUGUUUCUUUUCAUUUGAAUAUUUAAAUUUUAUGGUUUAUUAAAAAAUUAAAUAAA